GCAAACUCUGGAAGACCUUGGCUGAGGGUCUAGGUGGACUGUCUGAGGUAGGAGGUGGGGAGGGAGGAAGUGGUUGACCCUGGGGAAGGGUAGGAGACCUAUUUGGUAUCAGGGGAAAAACCAUUUGGAAUCCCCAAAUGAGGCCUCUGGACCUAGAUUCUGAGAAUGCCAUGUCCCAGGCUGGGAGAUUCAGUUUGGUUUCGAGGGUGGGCACCUACCUCCACCAGGAGAAGUGGAGGUGCUGUUUCAUUUCACACCUAGGGGCAAGCAGGGACUGUGAAGGGAAGAGACCUAUUGGGGGUCAGUGGAAUCAGGGUCUGAGGAAGGCAAAGGUACCACUGGACCCCGGCAGGAUUUUUGUCCCUCUGAUGGCUGUCAAGUCUUUCCUUAAAGGUGUGUGUAACGGUGACCUCCUCUCCGAGGUCCCCCAGUGUGUCCUCAAAGACAGCCUAAGUCAGGACCAUGGGACAGCCAGCAGGACUUGCGUCCUCCCCUCCCCCAGCCCCAUGGCAGUCUGGGACCCCUAGCCCCUGCUCUCUGCCUCCUGGGGCUGCUCCAGCCUGUCCCAGCCUUUUGAAAUCCUGGGCUAUCCCUUAGGUGCCACCCCAGUCUAAUAAUCAGAGCCCAGCAGGUCCAGUUAAUCAAAUGCAUUCUUUGAGCACCUGCAUGAGGUUCCAGCUAGAUCCAGAGGCAAAAUACACUUCCUGCCCUAAAGGACCCUACAGUGUAGUAGUGGAGGUAGGCGGGUCCAUAACUCACCACACUAUGGCAGAGUGGGGAAAAGUAAAGGCUUUAAGAGGUGUAGAAGAGGCUGUUUGGUAAGGUGGUGAGUUUCCCAUCACUGGAAGCCUUCAAGAAGAGGAUGGUAAGGGAUGCUAUAGAAGAGAUUUCUGCACUAUGCGUGUAUGGGUAUGUGUAGGGCGGUGCAGGCAGAGCAGGACUAGAUAAGAACUUUAGCGCUUUCUUUUUUUUGUUUUAUUCCUCCCCCCCGGCCCCAGCUCCCCUCUUCAACUUUAGCACUUUCUAAUGCUGACAUCUGUGAUUCUGUGACAUUCCCCACUUAGAGGAAGUUCGUCUGCGGUUUCACUGGGUAUGGUGGCUCCCUUGUUCACUGCACCCUGCAGCUAAACCAUAAAACAUGGGCUAUUCUUUGUCUCUGUGCAUGUCACCCCCAGUGCCAAGCCCCCAGCACAGACGUUGAGUGGAAUGGAAUAGACUCUUUGCUGGGCUGCUUGAGGAACAGAGGCAUCAGAUCUGAAGACAGCAUGUACACAGCCAUUCCCCAGAGUGGCUCUCCAUUCCCAGGCUCAGUGCAGGAUCCAGGCCUGCAUGUGUGGCGGGUGGAGAAGCUGAAGCCGGUGCCUGUGGCGCAAGAGAACCAGGGCGUCUUCUUCUCGGGGGACUCCUACCUAGUGCUGCACAAUGGCCCAGAAGAGGUUUCCCAUCUGCACCUGUGGAUAGGCCAGCAGUCAUCCCGGGAUGAGCAGGGGGCCUGUGCCGUGCUGGCUGUGCACCUCAACACGCUGCUGGGAGAGCGGCCUGUGCAGCACCGCGAGGUGCAGGGCAAUGAGUCUGACCUCUUCAUGAGCUACUUCCCACGGGGCCUCAAGUACCAGGAAGGUGGUGUGGAGUCAGCAUUUCACAAGACCUCCACAGGAGCCCCAGCUGCCAUCAAGAAACUCUACCAGGUGAAGGGGAAGAAGAACAUCCGUGCCACCGAGCGGGCACUGAACUGGGACAGCUUCAACACUGGGGACUGCUUCAUCCUGGACCUGGGCCAGAACAUCUUCGCCUGGUGUGGUGGAAAGUCCAACAUCCUGGAACGCAACAAGGCGAGGGACCUGGCCCUGGCCAUCCGGGACAGUGAGCGACAGGGCAAGGCCCAGGUGGAGAUUGUCACUGAUGGGGAGGAGCCUGCUGAGAUGAUCCAGGUCCUGGGCCCCAAGCCUGCUCUGAAGGAGGGCAACCCUGAGGAAGACCUCACAGCUGACAAGGCAAAUGCCCAGGCCGCAGCUCUGUAUAAGGUCUCUGAUGCCACUGGACAGAUGAACCUGACCAAGGUGGCUGACUCCAGCCCAUUUGCCCUUGAACUGCUGAUAUCUGAUGACUGCUUUGUGCUGGACAACGGGCUCUGUGGCAAGAUCUAUAUCUGGAAGGGGCGAAAAGCGAAUGAGAAGGAGCGGCAGGCAGCCCUGCAGGUGGCCGAGGGCUUCAUCUCGCGCAUGCAGUACGCCCCGAACACUCAGGUGGAGAUUCUGCCUCAGGGCCAUGAGAGUCCCAUCUUCAAGCAAUUUUUCAAGGACUGGAAAUGAGGGUGGGCGUCUUCCUGCCCCAUGCUCCCCUGCCCCCCACCACCUGCCUGCUUGCUUCUCUGGCUGCCUGGUCAGUGCAGAGGUGCCCCCUGCAGAUGUUCAAUAAAGGAGACAAGUGCUUUCCCAGCUCUUUUCCUGCA